GCGGGUGACUCCGACCCCUGGCUAGAGGGUAGGCGGCGUGGAGCAGCGCGCGCAAGCGAGGCCAGGGGAAGGUGGGCGCAGGUGAGGGGCCGAGGUGUGCGCAGGACUUUAGCCGGUUGAGAAGGAUCAAGCAGGCAUUUGGAGCACAGGUGUCUAGAAACUUUUAAGGGGCCGGUUCAAGAAGGAAAAGUUCCCUUCUGCUGUGAAACUAUUUGGCAAGAGGCUGGAGGGCCCAAUGGCUGCAAAAUCGCAACCCAACAUUCCCAAAGCCAAGAGUCUAGAUGGCGUCACCAAUGACAGAACCGCAUCUCAAGGGCAGUGGGGCCGUGCCUGGGAGGUGGACUGGUUUUCACUGGCGAGCGUCAUCUUCCUACUGCUGUUCGCCCCCUUCAUCGUCUACUACUUCAUCAUGGCUUGUGACCAGUACAGCUGCGCCCUGACUGGCCCUGUGGUGGACAUCGUCACCGGACAUGCUCGGCUCUCGGACAUCUGGGCCAAGACUCCACCUAUAACGAGGAAAGCCGCCCAGCUCUAUACCUUGUGGGUCACCUUCCAGGUGCUUCUGUACACGUCUCUCCCUGACUUCUGCCAUAAGUUUCUACCCGGCUACGUAGGAGGCAUCCAGGAGGGGGCCGUGACUCCUGCAGGGGUUGUGAACAAGUAUCAGAUCAAUGGCCUGCAAGCCUGGCUCCUCACGCACCUGCUCUGGUUUGCAAACGCUCAUCUCCUGUCCUGGUUCUCGCCCACCAUCAUCUUCGACAACUGGAUCCCACUGCUGUGGUGCGCCAACAUCCUUGGCUAUGCCGUCUCCACCUUCGCCAUGGUCAAGGGCUACUUCUUCCCCACCAGCGCCAGAGACUGCAAAUUCACAGGCAAUUUCUUUUACAACUACAUGAUGGGCAUCGAGUUUAACCCUCGGAUCGGGAAGUGGUUUGACUUCAAGCUGUUCUUCAAUGGGCGCCCCGGGAUCGUCGCCUGGACCCUCAUCAACCUGUCCUUCGCAGCGAAGCAGCGGGAGCUCCACAGCCAUGUGACCAAUGCCAUGGUCCUGGUCAACGUCCUGCAGGCCAUCUACGUGAUUGACUUCUUCUGGAACGAAACCUGGUACCUGAAGACCAUUGACAUCUGCCAUGACCACUUCGGGUGGUACCUGGGCUGGGGCGACUGUGUCUGGCUGCCUUAUCUUUACACGCUGCAGAAGAGAACACGGAGGCAAGGCGUGUGUCAGAGGCAGAGCUGGGGUUUGACCCCAGGCCGCUGGGCCCCCGAGCCCACACUCCUGUCCUCUCCCUGGGCAAAGCACCGCUUGACCCCUUCCCCCUCGCCCCCCAGGGUCUGUACUUGGUGUACCACCCCGUGCAGCUGUCCACCCCGCACGCCGUGGGCGUCCUGCUGCUGGGCCUGGUGGGCUACUACAUCUUCCGGGUGGCCAACCACCAGAAGGACCUGUUCCGCCGCACGGAUGGGCGCUGCCUCAUCUGGGGCAGGAAGCCCAAGGUCAUCGAGUGCUCCUACACAUCCGCCGAUGGGCAGAGGCACCACAGCAAGCUGCUGGUGUCGGGCUUCUGGGGCGUGGCCCGCCACUUCAACUACGUCGGCGACCUGAUGGGCAGCCUGGCCUACUGCCUGGCCUGUGGCGGCGGCCACCUGCUGCCCUACUUCUACAUCAUCUACAUGGCCAUCCUGCUGACCCACCGCUGCCUCCGGGACGAGCACCGCUGCGCCAGCAAGUACGGCCGGGACUGGGAGCGCUACACCGCCGCAGUGCCUUACCGCCUGCUGCCUGGAAUCUUCUAAGGGCACGCCCUAGGGAGAAGCCCUGUGGGGCUGUCAAGAGCGUGUUCUGCCAGGUCCAUGGGGGCUGGCAUCCCAGCUCCAACUCGAGGAGCCUCAGUUUCCUCAUCUGUAAACUGGAGAGAGCCCAGCACUUGGCAGGUGUCCAGUACCUAAUCACGCUCUGUUCCUUGCUUUUGCCUUCAAGGGAAUUCCGAGUGUCCAGCACUGCCGUAUUGCCAGCACAGACGGAUUUUCUCUAAUCAGUGUCCCUGGGGCAGGAGGAUGACCCAGUCACCUUUACUAGUCCUUUGGAGACAAUUUACCUGUAUUAGGAGCCCAGGCCACGCUACACUCUGCCCACACUGGUGAGCAGGAGGUCUUCCCACGCCCUGUCAUUAGGCUGCAUUUACUCUUGCUAAAUAAAAGUGGGAGUGGGGCGUGCGCGUUAUCCAUGUAUUGCCUUUCAGCUCUAGAUCCCCCUCCCCUGCCUGCUCUGCAGUCGUGGGUGGGGCCCGUGCGCCGUUUCUCCUUGGUAGCGUGCACGGUGUUGAACUGGGACACUGGGGAGAAAGGGGCUUUCAUGUCGUUUCCUUCCUGCUCCUGCUGCACAGCUGCCAGGAGUGCUCUGCCUGGAGUCUGCAGACCUCAGAGAGGUCCCAGCACCGGCUGUGGCCUUUCAGGUGUAGGCAGGUGGGCUCUGCUUCCCGAUUCCCUGUGAGCGCCCACCCUCUCGAAAGAAUUUUCUGCUUGCCCUAUGACUGUGCAGACUCUGGCUCGAGCAACCCGGGGAACUUCACCCUCAGGGGCCUCCCACACCUUCUCCAGCGAGGAGGUCUCAGUCCCAGCCUCGGGAGGGCACCUCCUUUUCUGUGCUUUCUUCCCUGAGGCAUUCUUCCUCAUCCCUAGGGUGUUGUGUAGAACUCUUUUUAAACUCUAUGCUCCGAGUAGAGUUCAUCUUUAUAUUAAACUUCCCCUGUUCAAAUAA